UGGCACCGCACUCGCUCGGUUCUAGUGCGCCUUUCCGGCCUCCGUGGCCCCAGGAGGCGAGCGAAUCGCUGCUUUCUCCUGCAGAAGCUUCUGACGCCUCUCCCACAUCUGCUCGCGGCUCUCUAUUCCCUUCGAGGUAGUUUUCCUUCUCAUAGCCACCACUUUUUGGUCUCAACCCUGGCGUCCAGGAAUGCGGGGUGGGUGCUUAAGGCCUGGCUUUGCUUCUUAGAUGCCAUAGAUGCUGAUAAUUCUACGUACAGUCACGCAGCCUGAUUCCUGAUUCGUGGACAGACUCUCCCAGUGCCGUGCUCGCCCCUUUCCCCUCGCUCUGGCUCUGGCUCUCGCUCUCUCAGGAGGCUCAGCCUGACCGCGGGCUUCUCAGGAGCCCAUUCCCCGGGCUGCUGUCGCUCCAUGCCUCAAGGUUUGAACACAUAGCUGGAGUGGCCCCUUACUUUUCAGUGUUGUUGCUACUCGUGUGCUAAGACCUCCCGAAAGCCUUGUGCCUGGCUUCUGACUCCUGACAUGUACGUUAGGAAGAUAGUACUUAUAUUAAAUAAUAAAAAUAAUAAAACAAACACACACUCCAUUUGACUUCUAAAGUGCUAUCAAACUUGAGAAGUAGGCAGAAUGGCUGAUUCAUAAUAGGGGAAACUGGUUUUACAAACUACUUUUCAUCCAGAAUGGCAUACUUCUUUUUUAUUAUAAAUACGAUGAUGAAACCUAAAAUAUCCCCAAUAAAAGCGAGGAUGGGUUGUGAUAUAUCUGUUCUUCCUGAGGUAGCCUGCAGUUGAAGAUAGUCGGUUCCAGAAAACAUUGGCAUGAGGCACCGGAAGUGAUAUUCUGGACAAGGUGAUUAGAUGAGGUUCUAAAGUUGUGAGGUGCUUUUUUGAAAAUUAGCAACAUUAUCUUUGAUGAAUGAGGUUGUUUUCUUAAAAGUAAGUGGUUGAAAAAACUUACAGUCCACAGAUGACACCUAUCAAAAGCAUACUGAAUUUAGAUUAGUAAUUUUGAUUGUAAGAUAGUUCUGUGAGCAGACAAAAGAUGGGUUCUUUUCCCUCCCUAUUGGUUUUUAAGCCAUUUCAGGUUUCGUUUAUCUGAUAAGACGUGGCGAGAGAGAAGCGUAAUAAUGGAAAAGCUAAAUUUUCUUUUUUUUGUAAAUGCUUUUGAGCUAAAGAUUUUUAAAAAGGAUAUAUAGAUGCCAUUUAUGAUUAAAUUUAUUGGGUGAAUCUGUCAAGACCGCAAACUUUGUUAGUUUGGGGUAAAAUGCUUUGCUUUGGGAGCUUUCAUGUUGUUUGAGGUUCUUUGGGGGUAUAGUUUAAAUUAAAGCACAAUAUAAUUCUAGUACCACUGCAAAAUAACCUCAGAGAGUAUUGUUUGUUUUGUGCAUUAGCAAGCUGACAUGCUUCUAGUUGCUAGAUUCCAAAGGUAAUUUUUUUUUUGUUUUGGAAAAGCUUUUGAUGAAUUUAAGUCUGAAUUAUUUGAAAUAAUAGUGUAUCAUAUGAAUACUUGCUCUUCACCUUCACAUACUUAGAGAACCCUGCAGUAAUUUGAAUCCAAUCUAGUAUUCCAUUGAAGUGAGUAUGACUAUGAAGAUGCCGCAUACUCUUAAGAGCAUUUACCUAGGGUGUCGUAAUCACAUUAUAAAAUAAAAUUGAUGGCUUAUUUUGCAAAUGCUAUCAAAGCACUUGUUCAGUGAACUCUGGAAUGAAGUUUUUUUUUUUUUUUAAAGUGACUUUCAACAAGUUUUUAUUUUCUAGCUUCUAAUGAAUGCCUACUACUAUACCAGGUAUUGUGGAGAAUAGAACAGAAACAGCAAUUUACCAGUUGGGUAAAUUGCUUACCCAAUGGUAAAUUACCGAUGGGUAAAUUGCUUAGCCAUUGGAAAAAGGAAAAUACAUAUAUGAGACACCAUGGUCAACAAUUGGAACAGAGUCAUAUUGAAUAAGGACUGAAAGAGUUAAGAGUAAAGGGAGAAUACUGUAGGCUGGAUUUUUCUGAGAAAGCUUUGUAGAGAAAGUCAUACUUGAUUUGGCUCUUAAUAGAAGUAUAAGCUUUCUUAGAAGGUGGAAGAGUUCAGCAUAGCAUGAGCUAAGGCACUUGAUUUUCUAAUCCUUUUGCAUAUUUUCUCCUAGGUAAACCUAAAGGAGAAGAGGACUGUCAGUGGCAAUUAACUUCUUUGUAGUGGGCAUAAUUUUCUAUGAUAAACUACAUACUAAAUUAACAAAUUAAAUAUAAUUUCACAGAUAUACAUGCUAUAGAAAUCAGGCUUUAAAAUAAUCAUCCUAUUUCCUGAGGCAAGUGAGAAUGUUUUCUAAGCAGAUAUAGGUAGAGUGUUAAGUUCACAUGUUUUUGUAACCUGUACAUUUUUUUUUACUGUCUAUUAAGAGACAGUUAUAUUCUAAGUGUUUCAUACAACACUGGUCUGAUAGUACAUUAGAUUAUUAAUAUGCUCCAAAGACUAUUUCUUGAUAAAAUAAAUUAGGGAAAUUUUAUAAGCAACAUUCAUUUUGAUUCAUUAGUAUAUGAUAACUUAGUUUUUAGUACUACAUUUAGUACUGCUAUUGCUACCAUUUUCUGAAAACAAAGGGAGGGGUAUGUCAGAGUCCCACAAAUUCAUAUCUGUCAAAGUUCUAAUAUCAUGUUAUUAAUGUAUAUAUUAAUAAUUGACAACAUCAAUGUUUAAACUGCAAUUACAAACCUCUGCAAAGCUUAUUUUGGUACAUUUCUAACAACCUUCCGCUAUAUUGAAAAUUAGUCAGAUGACUAAUUGUCUCCUAGGUUUUAGUCAGCCAUUGUAAGUUGACAUUUACACAGAAAAAUAACGAGGUAUGGAGUUAUUCCAUCCGUAGAGAGGUAUGUCUCCUAACAGAAAUUCACAUAUUAGAAUUCCAAAUAUAAAGAAUUCACAGAUUUACUCUGAGGAACAAUAUACUCAAACUUGAAAUUUUUGAGGCUUUAUACACCUUCUGUACCUUUUUUUUGGUAUCUUUUGCUGCCAGCAGUAGUCUUCUUUGAUUAAAGUUAACUUUAAUUCACAGUAGCUAAUAGUUUCUAGGCUCAACAAAUAUAAUUGUUAUUUUGAACAUCCUCUGCUUAGCACAUUAGCUAUUAAAUAAACAAGUUAUUAGAGAACAGAAUGGCUUAUCUGGACACAGUCAGCAAAUAGCUAUGAUUAUUGCUGGAAAUUAACCAGUUAACAGAUAGCAAAAUAUAUGGAGAAGGCAUUGGAGUAAAUCAUUUUUGCUAAGUAACUAUUGUACAUUUCUGGUCUUAUGACAGUAUCAAAGGGAUGAUCUUUGGAAAGAGGAGGGAAACUGCCAAGAAAAUUAAAAUUACCUCGUAUGUCAAAUUGUGGAAGAAAUAUGGAUAUGCUGUAUUCUGUUUGAAAGGAUUCAUCAUGAACCAGAAAAAAAUCAAUGAAAAGGGGCAUUUCACCUAGAUUAAAUUUUGCAAUUUUUAAAAAGCAUAUGAACAAAGAAACUAUCCUCCAAACAUCCAAAUAAGGAAGAAUACUUUACCUAACAAUAGGAACAAAUUAAAAAUAAUUGAUUCAGCCUAAGACUUUUUUUUCAGCGAAGAAGUAGUUUAAUAAUUGCAGGGCCAGCCAAAUAAGGAGAAAGGGAAAAAACUUCUCAAACCCAUCUCUCUGAGAAUUUGGAGGCUAGGUUUUUUUAAGGACACUUUGGCAGGCAGGGGAUAGGAAACUUUUAAGAAAUGAUUGACUGGGGAUGAAAUCACAGGGGUACCUAAAACUGUCUCGGCUUAGCUGAGUCAGUUCCUGGGAGGGGGCUGUCUUGGGACCAGGUGGCAUCUCUUGGUCAGCUCUUGGUCUGCUUAUAAAUCUGAAAAAUAUCUCAAAGACCAGUUUUUUUAAGUUUCAUAAUAGUGAUGUUAUCUAUAGGAGUAGUUGGAGAAGUGUAAAACUUGUGACCCCCAGUUACAUGACUCGGCAGCUGUAAGCAACUUAUAGAAAAACACAUAAAGCAAUGGCAGCAUCCCCCAGACAUCUAGACUAUGCCAGUCCUGUCUGCCUUCUGAGAGAGAUGAGAAAGAAACCCAUUUCUCAAGCAGUCCCCCCAAAAAGACAGAAUGUGGGACACAUGCCACAACUUUUUCCCUUCCUAGAGAGAAGCUGAGAAUUGGGAGUUUUCACCCUCUCGUUCUAUGCCGAGCUGGGAGGAGGGAGUAUGGAAGAAGCCAAGAAUUGGGAGUUUUCUGCUGAUGAUGCUAUGCUAAGCUGGGCAGAGAGACCAUGGCGAGAAAUAGACUAAAUAGCCAAGUUGCAAGAUACCACUGCUUCUUUUAAGAGUGAUGGGUUUCCCAGGUGAUACUUGAAAGAAGAGAUAACGACCACCUAUCUCCUUCAUCCUGGUUACACAGGAAGGUAGGCUAUGGACUCCUUUUGGCAUUUCUGCCUCAGCAACAGAGGAUAAAAGUCAUGUUGUGAUGGAUAAGUCACAAAAGUAAAAAAUACAGACGUGGACUACAGGCCUCCAAAGAAGAAUUGAGCAUGCUGAGGAUCGAUGCCAGACAUUGGACAUUUUUGAGGUGUUAAGAGAUGUGCAUGCUUCCAACAUUGUGAAGAUGUGUGUGCUUUCCAGUCACCUUCCACCAUGACUAGCAGAAAGAGUGUUUUCCUAUUGCCACCACAGCUAAGAAUGUGCUGGGUCACACCUGAAGCCAUCCCAGUACCAGGUUUCACCCAAGGCCCAUGGGACUGAUAACAUCUGAACAUACCAAACCACACAGUCAAACUCUUGCACCAUCGCUACCACGACAUUUUACUACAAAAGAAUGCCACUGCAUGUGGAUUCCAAGCAGGCUAAAAAGAAAAAGAACUGAUUAGACCUCAGACGACCCACUAAACGGGAUGACGGCCACAGCUGAGGUAGAGACACCAAAAAUGGAGAAGAGUGCCUCCAAGGAAGAGAAGCAGCAGCCUAAGCAGGACAGCACAGAGCAGGGCAAUGCUGAUUCUGAAGAGUGGAUGAGCUCUGAGAGUGACCCUGAACAGAUAAGCCUUAAGAGUAGCGACAACAGCAAGAGCUGCCAACCUAGGGAUGGUCAGUUGAAGAAAAAGGAGAUGCACUCCAAGCCACACCGCCAGCUCUGUCGAUCACCCUGCCUAGAUCGUCCAAGUUUCUCCCAGAGCAGCAUUUUACAGGAUGGUAAACUUGACUUGGAGAAGGAAUACCAAGCUAAGAUGGAGUUUGCGCUAAAGCUGGGCUAUGCAGAGGAACAGAUUCAAUCAGUGCUAAACAAGCUGGGCCCAGAAUCACUUAUUAAUGAUGUAUUGGCAGAGCUUGUCAGACUUGGGAACAAAGGUGAUUCAGAAGGGCAGAUCAACUUGAGUCUGUUAGUGCCUCGUGGGCCCAGCUCCAGAGAGAUUGCAAGCCCUGAAUUGUCUCUUGAAGAUGAAAUAGAUAACAGUGACAAUUUGAGGCCAGUUGUCAUUGAUGGAAGUAAUGUGGCAAUGAGCCAUGGGAAUAAAGAAGAAUUCUCCUGCAGAGGAAUACAACUUGCUGUGGAUUGGUUUCUAGAUAAAGGCCAUAAAGAUAUUACUGUAUUUGUGCCUGCAUGGAGAAAGGAGCAAUCCCGCCCUGAUGCACCAAUUACAGAUCAAGAUAUUCUACGAAAACUGGAGAAGGAAAAGAUUCUUGUCUUCACACCAUCCCGAAGAGUCCAAGGCAGGAGGGUUGUCUGCUAUGAUGACCGGUUCAUAGUCAAACUGGCUUUUGAUUCUGAUGGCAUCAUUGUGUCCAAUGAUAACUACCGAGACCUUCAAGUUGAAAAGCCAGAAUGGAAGAAGUUUAUAGAGGAGCGGUUGCUGAUGUAUUCUUUUGUGAAUGACAAAUUUAUGCCUCCAGAUGAUCCAUUAGGACGCCACGGCCCAAGCCUUGAAAAUUUCUUAAGAAAGAGACCCAUUGUUCCUGAGCAUAAGAAGCAACCAUGUCCUUAUGGCAAAAAAUGCACCUACGGCCACAAGUGCAAAUACUACCAUCCGGAGCGGGCCAACCAACCCCAGCGUUCGGUGGCUGAUGAGCUCCGCAUCAGUGCCAAACUGUCCACAGUGAAAACUAUGAGUGAAGGCACCCUGGCCAAGUGUGGCACAGGGAUGUCUAGUGCCAAAGGUGAGAUAACCUCAGAGGUCAAACGUGUGGCCCCCAAGCGCCAAUCAGAUCCCAGCAUCCGGUCUGUGGCUAUGGAGCCUGAGGAAUGGCUGUCCAUUGCCCGUAAGCCUGAGGCUAGUUCUGUCCCCUCGCUUGUGACUGCCCUAAGUGUUCCCACAAUCCCACCCCCCAAAAGCCAUGCAGUGGGUGCACUCAACACCCGUUCGGCCAGCAGCCCAGUGCCAGGAUCCUCCCAUUUCCCCCACCAGAAGGCCUCUUUGGAGCAUAUGGCCAGCAUGCAGUAUCCUCCCAUCUUGGUUACCAACAGCCAUGGGACCCCUAUUAGCUAUGCUGAGCAAUACCCAAAGUUUGAAUCCAUGGGGGACCAUGGCUACUAUUCAAUGUUAGGUGACUUCUCCAAACUGAACAUCAACAGCAUGCAUAACCGAGAGUAUUACAUGGCUGAAGUAGACCGGGGGGUGUAUGCCCGGAAUCCUAACCUCUGUUCUGACAGCCGUGUGAGCCAUACCAGGAAUGACAACUAUUCCUCUUACAACAACGUGUAUUUGGCUGUAGCUGAUACCCAUCCUGAAGGCAAUUUGAAGCUGCACCGCUCAGCAUCCCAGAACCGACUUCAGCCUUUUCCUCAUGGUUACCAUGAAGCCUUAACACGAGUGCAGAGCUAUGGCCCAGAGGAUUCUAAGCAAGGCCCCCACAAACAGUCAGUCCCCCACUUAGCUCUGCAUGCCCAGCACCCAUCAACUGGAACACGUUCCAGCUGUCCUGCAGACUACCCCAUGCCUCCCAAUAUCCAUCCUGGGGCAACCCCCCAGCCAGGCCGUGCCCUGGUGAUGACUCGGAUGGAUAGCAUUUCCGACUCCCGCCUCUAUGAGAGCAACCCCGUGAGGCAAAGACGACCUCCCCUGUGCCGGGAACAGCAUGCCAGCUGGGACCCGCUGCCCUGUACAACUGACUCCUAUGGCUACCACUCCUAUCCCUUGAGUAACAGCCUCAUGCAACCAUGUUAUGAGCCAGUCAUGGUACGGAGCGUGCCUGAAAAGAUGGAGCAGCUUUGGAGGAAUCCUUGGGUUGGAAUGUGCAAUGAUUCCAGGGAGCAUAUGAUCCCAGAACACCAGUAUCAGACCUACAAGAACCUCUGCAAUAUUUUCCCUUCUAACAUCGUCCUUGCAGUGAUGGAGAAGAAUCCCCACACAGCAGAUGCCCAGCAACUGGCAGCCUUGAUUGUUGCUAAGCUUAGGGCUGCACGUUGAUAUGACAUAGUACUUAUUUCUUUAUACAAAUAUGAAUAUUAAUACUAAUAAUACACUAAUACAAUAAUUAUAGUAACUAAUAAUUUGUGUUGCGCUUUACAAGUUAGAGUGUUUAUAUCAUUUAAGCGCUUAACAACCCUGUGAGGUACGUCUUACUAACAUCCUCUUUUAUAGAGAAGGAAGGUGAAGGUCAGUGAAAUUAAGUGGCUAGCCAGGGUCACACUGCUAGCAAAUGACUAAGUCAAGACACACACCCAAGUCCUCUAAAUCCAAGUCCCAUGCCCCUUUGCACUGCACCAUGCAGGUAAUGGAGGACAAAACCCAGGGGGAGAGGUCUAGAUGUAAGAAAUCCCAGAGGAUUCCAUUACCAGAGUUUUCCUUUUUCUCUUUUCGUUUCUUUCUUUCUUUCUUUAUUUUUUUUUUUUGAGACAGAAUCUCACUCUGUUACACAGGCUGGAGUGCAGUGGCACUAUCUCUGCUCACUGCAACCUCCACCUCCAGGGUUCAAGUGAUUCUAUGGCCUCAGCCUCCCAGGUAGCUGGGAUUACAGGCGUGCACCACCAUGCCCAGCUAAUUUUUGUAUUUUUAGUAGAGACGUGGUUUCACCGUGUUGGCCAGGCUGGUCUCAAACUCCUGGCCUCAAGUGAUCCGCCCACCUUGGCCUCCUAAAGUGCUGGGAUUACAGGUGUGAGCCACUGCGCCCAGCCUACCAGAGUUUUCGUAGUCACAUAUUCUAUAUUACAAAGUAUGGAUGAUAUAUCCAAUUUAGAGAGCAAAAGCAUCAGGAUCAGAUCAUAUGUUGAAUUAACCUUUUAGGUUUUUUCUAAUAGAAAUAUUUAAAGCUAUUUAAAAGUAAAUGCAUACUUUAUUGCAUGGAUAUCUGAUCACUCAAUCUAUAUUAAUGAAACUAUAGGGUCACAUUGAAGCUUCUAGAACUAUAUUUUAAAGCUAUUAUUAGCAAUUAUAUUGCAUGUAUGAAUAUAUAUAUUUGGUUUGAGAUGUGUGUGUAUCUCUGUAUAACCUUUUAUAUAGUGAUAAUGAGAGGGUAGGCUCUACACAGUCCUUCGUCUAUAGCUGUAUAGGUCACUAAUCUGACUUGAUGAUUUUAAGUCACAUUUCAUAGUUUUAACUAGUUAUGAGAGAGAAAUUAUAUGGCAAUAUUUGAACAUUGCUUUCUUAGGCACCAGAGCAAAGCAACUCUGUUUCCUUUGCACAUUUUACCUGCCAACAUUUAUUAACAGUUCUUACCUUCCAAGUCUCUUCACCUUAGCAAAUUAGGGAUCAGGUUGCAGUCUUCUGCAGAGAAACUGAUGGUUAAGCUCAAGUUCCAAGCAUAGUAUGUGUGUGCUACACAAGCUCAGAAGAGUUUGACAAGGACCAGGGGACUUACUACCACAAUCCACUUCCCUUAUCCCAGGAGAGAUGGCCAAACCCAUGUGGCAUUAAAUGGUGAAUAAAAAAGCUUCACUCAAGGAGGGACUAUUGGAUGCUCUUUGGACUUCUGACCUAUGCAGUAUUCAACAUCAUUGGAUGAAAUGUAAUGGAGGACAGUGCACAGCCAUGUAUCCACUUUCUCUUCCUGUCCACCCUUUGGGUAAUAAGGUCAAUCAUUGGUGGAACAGAAUUUCUCUAGGAAACAAAACCAGGGGAUUUUAUUUGUGGAAAAAGGAAGUUUCCAAAAGGGGAUACUGCAUCUUUACUAAUAGCUGGCUCAGUUACUCACUUUAAAUCCAUGCAAAGAGUGCACUUGCUGUUAAAUAAUUGUUAAAUGAGUUAUUAGAAGGCAGGACUUUUGGUUUGGGCGACACCAUUUGCGCAACUUGUAUCUUGCUCAGGGUGGAAAACUUCAUAGCUAAAUGCCUCUAGAAGAGGUGUUUAUUGUUUUUUUUAAGCUGCACUAAAUGAAUUCCCUUUUUGAAUCCAUUGUAUAUUUCAAUAUUUCGAACCAUGAUCAGCUCACUAUUUCCUGAGCUGGAACUUGCUAACUUCUAUGAUCGUUUUUUCAUGAAAGUUGAGAAGGCCGGGCCUUGGCCUUUUGUUUCUUCAUGAGAAGGUGUGACACUGCCUAUAAAUGUUUCUUACUGUGAAACACUCUGAAUGUGAGGCUGUAGUCAGGGUUGUUUCUGGUGGUUUGACAAUGGCUUGCAUGCUGCUUUCUGGCUUUCUGUCUCUGUCCAAGUUGAUCAAUACUGCAUCUUAACCAAUGUUUCACUUGAGUUAACCACAGCUUUACAUUCUAUCUCCUAUCUUCUGAUCUUCGUAUACCCCAGCAUAUUGAAAAAGAGUAAAAGUAUUUUCUAUCAAUCAGGUAGAUCCACAGAGUGACAGUUGCCACUGCAGUGCUUGCUAUUUCACACAAACACCAUUUCAUACCUUCAACUUCUUGGACUUUCUAAAUCGGACUCGUGUCUAAAUCAGGGUAUUUGACAAUCUCAGAUGAUGCUACUGCCUAUGUGCCAGUUAGUUCAUCUUCCUACCAAGAUCAUGAAUGGCACCACACUAUCCACUAGCUGUACAAUUUACAGAGAAGCACAAGAUUCAUCUUGUCACCUACAAUUCGUCUUGAACAUGUUCAUAUUUAGUACUCAGAAACUGUGUAAGCUCCUCCCAAUACAGAAAAUAUUUUUUAAGGCAGCAUAUGUAUUUCUGAUUUACUAAAAACGAUUGUCAUUCUCCUCUCAUUCUUCUUUUUGGUAUGAACCAAAAGCGGCUAGGAGCAAUGCCUCAAAUAACCAGAAAUGACCUUUUGUUGAUACAAAUUGUAUCUCUUUUUUUCCUGAUUGUAUAGAAACAAAUGUACAAAACUCAUCUGAAGCUAGGUUUGGCACUGAAUUUUCACCAUGAGGUUUGUGGCACUGUGUGUCACAGGGAAGUAGCUCAGGGGUUGUGAGGGAGCUUUUAUUUCUAAAGGGCAGUAGUAAUUUAUAGACAAAAACAAUUUUUCAAGGCCUCUUUAUUACCACUGCACAGCUAUCAUGUGUAAAAUUUCAAGCAUUAUAUUGCAUAAGUUCUCUUUAGCCUAUUAAAUUUAAUAUGUCCUUGCAAAAGGGAUUUUGUGUAAAAAGUGUCAGUGUUAGUGACUCAUCUGCAAGAAUCUACAAAUGGAGCUAUACAACUAUGAAUACAUAAAUACAGCAUGGUUCCUAGUUAUUAGAGAAACAUUUUCUUUAUAUUGAGGUCUACGCACUUCUUGACUUUCCAUUUUGUCUGUAAUUAUAAAACAGCAAAUAACAAAGAAGCAUUGGGACCCCCUCGGCUGCCUUGAUAAUAAAAUCAAGCUUCCUUCAUGGGACUAAGCAUGUGUCCUUCAGGAUACUUACCUCUAAGCACUCAGCAGGGGUUACUACAAAGCGUUUUGUGUGGUUUUCAAAAAACAGUGUAUUUUGCAAGAGGUGCUUUGUAAUUUUAAUUAUUUCACUGAUUUUCUGACCUCAUAGGAAGUCUGUGCCUGUUGAGGCCUUCAAUUUUGUAGCUUUUCUGAUUUUUUUUCUUCUUUUUGUGAUUUUGUUGUUGUUUUCAUUUUGAUCUAAAGGAGAAGUGUGACCCCGGAGUGGCAUGGUCAAUCCAGGGCACCCUUUCUGUAAGACAACUCAAAGGAAAAGAAGCCUUUUCAAAGGUAAUAUCGAGCCAUUGCACUCUCUCUUAAGGUGCCAGGUAUGGGAGAAUGACAGAUGCCUUAUGGAAAUGGUCUACAAAACUUUUCUUCUUCUAAGUAAUAAAACACAUAGCAUGAUUCUCUCUCCCUCUCUCUCUCUCUCUCUGCCCACCCCCUGCUAGUUUCCAGGAGAAUACUUCUCUAAAAUUCAUUUUUUUCUAUUUUGGAAUAAAUUAUCUUUAUACAGUAAUUCAAACACUGAUUUCCAUUAACCUUUGGCCCUGAGUUUUCUUCUAACAUAGAAGAGUUCAUUUUGAGAGGCACUCAGUUACCAUUCAAUCUGUGCUGUAAGUAUGGGACUUUGUACAAAUGCCCUUUUUGAGGGCCAAAAAUUUCAAUACACUUUGUUCUACUUUGUGAACCAGGUCUGGAUCUGCACAGAGAAAGUAAUGCUGAGCUGUCCAAAGAGUCCGCUCAGGUCUCCCUCCUAACCCUCCUCUGCCUUCCCCUAGUUUGCUUAUCCUCACGUCUGACACUGAGGAGUGCAUAGUCUUCAACUGAAAUGGCACUACAGUUAGUUCUCAUUGGAAACAAACAAGUGUAUUUCUGGAACCUGCUCGUCUAAAAUAGUCAAUGCCUUUGUAAAGACUCAGCAUAUUCAAUAUCUAUUGUAUGGUAGCUAGCUAUAUACAUAGAUUGACUAUUUUUAGUCCUGGUUUGUGUAUUGUUGAGCUAUAGUAGUUUGCUUUAUCCAUUUGUGGGAUUAAACAAUACUGUUUAAUGGUUGUAAACUUUUAUAAAAUCUCUUUGGGUUUUUUGUUUGACCCAAACAUAAUGUAAGUCUUAAUGACAAAAUACACAAAGUUAACCAGAGGUGAGUGAAAAUAUAGCCCUUCCCCAGUUUUGUCUGCCCCUAUAAUGCACGUGCAUUGCUUUGUAAUAUGCUCUCGCUAGCAUGAAUGUGCUAUGACUACUUCAUGAGGUUUUGUUUCACCUAUAAUUGUGAUGGAAAAUGCUGUAUUGCUGACAACAAUGAACUGUAACCACAGUUAUUUACUGCAUAAACUAUUUGUGUACUAACCA